CCUCUAGCAACUUUGGGACGUGAGAGCUUGGGCCUGGGCCUGGCUGACUCAGGUCAGUGGAGCGACCUGAGUCGCGUCCCAAAGAGUUGGAGGUCCCACCCUGAGCCAGGUUCAGAACCCUGAGGCAGAGCAGUGGGGUCCCCUAUAGUCCCACCCCUGCUGUCACGCCUUGAAGGCCCUAAACAGCCUUGAGAGGAUGUGGCUUACCCUGAAUGUCCAAAUCUGAGGUCCCAUUGAAGCAAGGAUCUUGCUUUGAAGGGUGUUGCCUGUAGUGAGCUGAGGAUGGAGUCCCAGGACUGGUCAAGUAGCAAGGUGAAGAUCCUGAGCCCUCAGUAGACAGGGCUGCACGGAGCGUUUCAGCAGAGGGCUUUGGUUGCAAGACUGGCUGCCCCAGGUCAGCGGAGAAAGGAGUCCCAGGCUCUGUGGGGAGUGAAGGUGCCCACCUCCUGCACCCUCUUGCCUGCUGCCCCUAAGCACAGUCAUCAUGCCUCGCGGUCAGGCGAGUAAGCGCCGUGCCCGUGAGAAACGCCGCCAGGCUCGAGGUGAAGACCAAUGUCUCGGGGGUGCUCAAGCCACCGCAGCAGAGAAGGAAAAGCUGCCAUCCUCCUCCUCUCCUGCAUGCCAGAGUCCUCCCCAGAGCUUCCCCAAUGCAGGCAUUCCUCAGGAGUCCCAGAGAGCCAGCUACCCCAGCUCUCCUGCUUCAGCUGUUUCACUCACAAGUUCUGAUGAAGGUGCCAAGGGCCAAAAGGGGGAAAGUCCCAACUCCUUCCAUGGCCCGUCCUCCUCUGAGAGCACAGGAAGAGAUCUUCUGAACACGAAGACGGGCGAAUUGGUGCAGUUCCUCCUCAACAAGUAUAUAAGGAAAGAGCCCAUUACGAGGGAAGCCAUGCUGAAGGUUAUCAACAGAAAGUACAAGCAGCACUUCCCUGAGAUCCUCCGGAGAAGCACUGAGAACGUAGAGGUGGUCUUUGGCCUCUACCUGAAGGAAAUGGACCCCAGCCGUCAGUCCUAUGUGCUUGUUGGCAAGCUGGACUUUCCCAAUCAAGGAAGCUUGAGCGAUGGCGGGGGCUUUCCCCUGAGCGGGCUCCUGAUGGUUCUCCUGAGCACCAUCUUCAUGCAUGGCAACCGUGCCACUGAGGAAGAGAUGUGGGAAUGCCUGAAUGCAUUGGGGAUGUAUAAGGGUAGGAAGCACUUCAUCUAUGGGGAGCCCCAGGAGCUUGUCACCAAAGAUUUGGUGCGAGAGGGGUACCUGGAGUACCAGCAGGUGCCCAGCAGCGAUCCUCCACGCUACGAGUUCCUGUGGGGUCCCAGGGCCCGUGCUGAAACCAGCAAAAUGAAAGUCCUGGAGUUUGUGGCCAAGCUCAAUGAUACCGUUGCCAGUACCUACAAGUCCCGGUAUGAGGAGGCUCUGAGAGAGGAGGAAGAGCAAGCCAGAGCCAGAGCGGUAGCCAGGGAUAGCGCCAGGGCCAGGGCUAGCAGGUCCUUUCAGCCCUAGUGAAGUCUCAGGCAAUCCUCACUAAGAGAUUGAAAAGCCUGUCCACCAUCUCAGUAUUUGGGGGUGAGGUG